AGUGGACCCCUGGGCUGCUGCCAGCCCCGACCUGGCACUUGCUUGCCUGUGUCACUGUCAGGAUUUGUCUAGCGGCGCAUUCCCUGACAGGGGUGUGUUGGGGGGAGUCCUCUUUCCAACUGUCGAAAUGGUUAUCAAAGUGUUUGUUGCUACAUCUUCUGGGUCCAUAGCGAUUAGGAAGAAACAGCAAGAAGUAGUGGGUUUUUUGGAAGCGAAUAAAAUCGACUUUAAGGAAUUAGAUAUUGCUGGAGAUGAAGACAACAGGAGGUGGAUGAGAGAGAAUGUUCCUGGAGAGAAAAAACCUCAAAAUGGGAUUCCUUUGCCUCCCCAGAUCUUCAAUGAGGAGCAGUACUGUGGGGAUUUUGACUCUUUCUUCUCUGCAAAAGAAGAGAAUAUUAUUUAUUCCUUCCUUGGUUUGGCUCCUCCUCCAGACUCAAAGGGAUCAGAGAAGGCUGAAGAAGGUGGAGAAACUGAGGCACAAAAAGAGGGCAGUGAAGAUGUGGGCAACCUCCCUGAAGCCCAGGAGAAGAAUGAAGAAGAAGGAGAGACAGCCACAGAAGAGACGGAAGAAAUAGCCAUGGAGGGUGCGGAAGGGGAAGCCGAGGAGGAGGAAGAAACUGCAGAAGGAGAAGAGCCUGGAGAAGACGAAGAUUCCUAGGCCUUUUCAUGCUUCAUUUCUUCCACUUCUCCAGAAAAUGGAAGCUAUGAAGCAACAUUUCAAAUGUCUCUCCACAAACCAAACUCAACAGAAUACUUUGGCUUGAAGCCGGCACACCCAGGGUUACUGAGGACUUAUGCUGCCUGACCUGGUUAGAUGUACAUGGAGGUAUCUCCCGAAUCAUACAAAAUUAAAUGUGAAGACCGUUUAUGCAUACCUUCAUGUGCCUGACAGUCUUGGCUUUUGAAGAUUUUUUUUUCUUUUUUGCUCUGCAUAGCUAGACCAUCUUAUUAAUAAUACUCUGAAAAAAAUGAUUUCAAGGCAUGGAAGUUCUCUGUGAUACAACAAUAGUAUUUCUUCAAAUGCGCCUUAUGCUACUUAUCUCAGAAACAGGUUUUAAAAUGAAGUGCUUUCCAGAGAACCAUCAUAUAAAUAAAGAUUAAUAGAAAAA